ACUUCAGAGAAGCGGAGGAAUAAGAGAAGCAGCAGGACUUUAACAGAGACUAGAAUAUUUAAAUUUUUGCAAAACAUGCUCUUCUAAUUUGAUCAAAACAUUGAGGAUUGGUAAUGGCGUCUUCUAUCAGAAGGGGCCGAGGGGCCUGGACACGGCUGCUCUCGCUUCUGCUCCUCGCAGCCUGGGAGGUGGGGAGCGGCCAGCUCCGCUACUCCGUCCCCGAGGAGGCCAAACACGGCACCUUCGUGGGCCGCAUCGCGCAGGACCUGGGGCUGGAGCUGGAGGAGCUGGUGCCGCGCCUGUUCCGGGUGGCGUCCAAAAGACACGGGGACCUUCUGGAGGUAAAUCUGCAGAAUGGCAUUUUGUUUGUGAAUUCUCGGAUCGACCGGGAGGAGCUGUGCGGGCGGAGCGCGGAAUGUAGCAUCCACGUGGAGGUGAUCGUGGACAGGCCGCUGCAGGUUUUCCAUGUGGAAGUGGAGGUGAAGGACAUUAACGACAACCCGCCAAUAUUUCCAAUGACAGUAAAGACUAUCCGGUUUCCCGAAUCAAGGCUGCUUGAUUCUCGGUUUCCUCUAGAGGGAGCAUCUGAUGCAGAUAUAGGAGUAAAUGCUCUUCUCUCCUACAAGCUCAGCUCCAGUGAGUUUUUCUUCCUAGAUAUACAGGCAAAUGAUGAACUAAGCGAAUCUUUGUCUCUCGUGCUGGGGAAAUCGCUGGACAGAGAGGAAACUGCUGAGGUUAAUUUGUUACUGGUGGCUACUGAUGGGGGCAAACCUGAGCUCACGGGCACCGUUCAAAUACUUAUUAAGGUAUUAGAUGUAAAUGACAAUGAACCAACUUUUGCCCAAUCAGUUUACAAAGUAAAAUUGUUAGAGAAUACGGCAAAUGGGACCUUAGUGGUUAAGUUAAACGCUUCUGAUGCAGAUGAAGGACCGAACAGCGAGAUUGUGUAUUCACUCGGUAGUGAUGUGUCCUCCACUAUACAGACUAAGUUUACCAUAGAUCCCAUCUCAGGGGAAAUCAGAACUAAGGGAAAAUUAGAUUAUGAAGAAGCAAAGUCCUACGAGAUUCAGGUCACUGCAACUGACAAAGGAACCCCUUCAAUGUCAGGACAUUGUAAAAUUUCAUUAAAACUUGUGGACAUCAAUGAUAACACACCAGAAGUCUCAAUAACGUCUCUCUCACUUCCCAUCUCAGAGAACGCUUCCCUGGGCACUGUCAUUGCUCUCAUCACGGUGUCGGAUCGCGACUCUGGUACGAAUGGACAUGUCACCUGCUCCCUGACGCCCCACGUCCCUUUCAAGCUGGUGUCCACCUUCAAGAAUUACUACUCGUUGGUGCUGGACAGCGCCCUGGACCGCGAGAGCGUGUCAGCCUAUGAGCUGGUGGUGACCGCACGGGACGGGGGCUCGCCUUCACUGUGGGCCACCACCAGCGUGUCCAUCGAGGUGGCCGACGUGAACGACAACGCGCCGGCGUUCGCACAGCCUGAGUACACAGUAUUCGUGAAGGAGAACAACCCGCCGGGCUGCCACAUCUUCACGGUGUCAGCGUGGGAUGCGGACGCGCAGGAGAACGCGCUGGUGUCCUACUCGCUGGUGGAGCGGCGGGUGGGCGAGCGCGCGUUGUCGAGCUACGUUUCGGUGCACGCGGAGAGCGGCAAGGUGUACGCGCUGCAGCCGCUGGACCACGAGGAAGUGGAGCUGCUGCAGUUCCAGGUGAGCGCGCGGGAUGCGGGCGUGCCGCCUCUGGGCAGCAACGUGACGCUGCAGGUGUUCGUGCUGGACGAGAACGACAACGCGCCGGCACUGUUGGCGCCUAGGGCUGGCACCGCUGCUGGCGCAGUGAGUGAGCUGGUGCCGUGGUCGGUGGGUGCAGGGCACGUGGUGGCGAAGGUGCGCGCAGUGGACGCUGACUCAGGCUACAACGCGUGGCUUUCGUACGAGCUUCAGCUGGGUACUGGCAGCGCUCGCAUCCCGUUCCGCGUGGGGCUAUACACGGGUGAGAUCAGCACGACACGUGCCCUAGACGAGGCUGACUCCCCUCGACACCGCCUACUCGUGCUGGUGAAGGACCACGGCGAACCAGCGUUGACAGCCACGGCCACCGUGUUAGUGUCGUUGGUGGAAAGUGGCCAGGCACCCAAGGCCUCGUCGCGGGCGUGGGUGGGCGCCGCGGGCUCAGAGGCUACGCUGGUGGAUGUCAACGUGUACCUGAUCAUCGCCAUCUGCGCGGUAUCCAGCCUGUUGGUGCUCACGGUGCUGCUGUACACUGCGCUGCGGUGCUCGGUGCCACCCACCGAGGGUGCGCGCGCGCCAGGAAAGCCCACGCUGGUGUGCUCCAGCGCCGUGGGGAGCUGGUCUUACUCGCAGCAGAGGCGGCAGAGGGUGUGCUCUGGGGAGGACCCCCCCAAGACGGACCUCAUGGCCUUCAGCCCUAGCUUAUCUCAAGGUCCAGACUCCGCAGAAGAGAAACAGCUCUCAGAAUCAGAAUACGUAGGAAAGCCACGACAGCCCAACCCUGACUGGCGUUACUCUGCCUCCCUGAGAGCAGGCAUGCACAGCUCUGUGCACCUAGAGGAGGCUGGCAUUCUACGGGCUGGUCCAGGAGGGCCUGAUCAGCAGUGGCCAACAGUAUCCAGUGCAACACCAGAACCAGAGGCAGGAGAAGUGUCCCCUCCAGUCGGUGCGGGUGUCAACAGCAACAGCUGGACCUUUAAAUACGGACCAGGCAACCCCAAACAAUCCGGUCCCGGUGAGUUGCCCGACAAAUUCAUUAUCCCAGGAUCUCCUGCAAUCAUCUCCAUCCGGCAGGAGCCUACUAACAGCCAAAUUGACAAAAGUGACUUCAUAACCUUCGGCAAAAAGGAGGAGACCAAGAAAAAGAAGAAAAAGAAGAAGGGUAACAAGACCCAGGAGAAAAAAGAGAAAGGGAACAGCACGACUGACAACAGUGACCAGUGAGGUCCUCAAAUGGAAACAAGCCACUUAGCCAGUUUUUGUAAUAAUGGCAAAUCUCUCCCAUGUAGCAAUUCCCUGCUCCUUUUUCCUAUCUACAUGAGCCCUCUUAGAGACCUCAGAAAUCUGCAGAAAGUUCCCUGUGUCUGUCUAGAACGCAUUUAACAGGUUUUGUCGUAAAAGCUUUACUAAGUCUGGUGUUAACUCUUUCUCUCCACUCUGGCUUGUUUUCAGAACCUAAAAAGCAGACCCAAGUUUCCUUUCUCCUCCGCCGCAAAGGAGAGGCUUCCCAGCCCCGCCAGUGAGAGGUUGGACUCUCUGCCCUGUGCUCCGGGGAUCCUGUCUUGAUGACACUUGCAGGGCAGGCUGAAAAGUUUUGAGAUUGAGCAGCUUGGGAGUUUGUGGCCACUGGGUAUGUGUGGCUACCGCGGGUAUGCGAGUGCCAGAUAUUGGCUGAGACGAGCCAGCUUAGACUAAUUGGUACAAGGAAGGCAAGAAAACAAAGACAAAUAAACAGCGGAAGUUAUCAGUAUGGAGGGGAAGUGUAAACUUAAAGGGACCAGACUUUCUAAAUCUUACAACUCAAGAGGUGGCAGCCACCCUCUAGGAGACAAAACUACCCCCACUGACAAGGCUUUAGGAGACCCUAAAGUCUGUUGGCUGUGACGUCAUUAUACCUAAAAUCUGCAUCAUACCUGCAAGCCAACAGUUCAGUGUUUUAACAGAGAACCACCCUGGGAAACAGAAGCAGAUCUGAUGUGUUUCCUAUACAUGUCCUGUGCUCACUUUAUUAAAAAUUCUUUUGCACACAAUGUUUAUGAAAAGGCCAGAUCCUUUUCCAAUACUUAUGCAAAAGCAAAAGAAAACCCCGACACCUCACCUUUCGCUGUUUGUUGUUUCAUAGAUUUAUUUAAAAAAAGAGAAAGUCUAUAGCUAUAAAUCUUUAAAGAGAAAUAUGAAUACAAUUCCCCUAAACUCUCCUCAAAAGAGAAUUCAGUCUACAGCCAUUUAAAUGAUCAUUGCUGCUACAGAAGUGCUUUAAGAGAAUUGCCUGAAACAUCUGUAUUAUAUCGGCCACCUGCCAAUCACAGCUUUACUCUUUCAGGUCACUCUGGGGCUGCCUCUUGCAUGUAUUACUAAAUAAAAUGAUCUCUCUUUCUCUCUCUCUCUCUCUUUUCUAAGAAACAAUUAUGUGCACUUUGAUACACAACCUUCUCUAACCAACUAUAUAUCAAGACCCAAAAAUUGAAGAAAAAUAUUGUUUUCUCAUACAGUGAGCAGAUUUUUCAAUCUACUAAUUCUGUGACUUGUCUUGGUGUGCUAGCCUACACCUUCUCUUUGGUUUAGUUUUCCUUUUCUAUAACACUCUGAAUUGCUAAUCUUACUAACACCUAUGAUGUUACCUGAAAUCAAUCUCCCAUAUGUAUGCUGUAUGCUAUGCUAAGACUCCUGAAAUAUACUUACUCUGUGCUUGUGUAUGUGAAUGUUAAUGCAACUAUUACCUAGAGUGAACUUUAAGCUUUAUUGUUGAAUGUAAUUCCAUUAUAUUUCCUUUUGUACACCUGUGAAAAAGUGGAGUAGUGUUUUUUUAACCAUUGUUAAUCAGCUUUUGUGUAUGAAAGACACAGUAAAAUUUCUUUCUUAAAUCAAGAUACUGGUGAUUCAAGGAAUUUUAUUUAUGGUCCAGCCAAGAGCCAUCUCGUGCCAAGACUUCUGCUGGCAAGGGAAUGGAUAAAGCUGUUUUGUUCUAGUAACAAUUUUGGAAUGAAUACUGACAAUAUUCCAUGAGGGUGUGCAAGCACAAAUUUUACCAAUCUGACCUCUUUGAAGUUGCAGAAUGCUUUGAAAUUCUAAUGGUAUCUGAAAUAUCAGCUCAUAGAAAGUAACAAAAUUUGCUGUCACCUUAAAUAAGACAUUUUAAUUUUGUUAUAAUGUACAAUUUAGAAGUUUGAUUAAUUAUAUUAUCUAUUUAGGCAUUAAUAUAAAAGAGGUAGGAGUCUGUUAUUUAAAAAAAGCAUUAAAUUUAAAAAAAAACUGUCUUGUCUACUUUUAGCUUCAUUCUCCCAUAUUUUGAAGGGUGUGUAACUUCAGCUCUGCAGGAUUGCAUGGGGUAAAACUUGUUACCAACACAUGUGAACCAUUGCUACAUUGUAGGUUGUGAUCAUUUUGCCCCACUGAAGCCCAUGUAUCUGACCUUACGUGCCUUUUGAACUAGGAGAAUCGGGCUAAUUUAUUAAUGAUGAUAAUUAUAAUGUAUCUGUACAGCACUUUUUACAUUUGCGAAGUGCUUUCCAAUCCAUGUUAGUUACUAGUUAUUACAGCUGUAAGGAUAAAACACGUCAUGUGGAUUCAUUUUGAAUUGGUGCUAUUGGUAUUUCCUCUGUUAUUGCUAAUAAAUGAAAAUGGUGGUAUGAAA